GCGCCUCCGCUCGCCUGUGGCUGCGUCGCGCGCUCUUCCUCGGAGCUACCCAGGCGGCUGGUGUGCAGCAAGCUCCGCGCCGACCCCUGACGCCUGACGCCUGUCCCCGGCCCGGCAUGAGCCGCUACCUGCUGCCGCUGUCGGCGCUGGGCACGGUAGCAGGCGCCGCCGUGCUGCUCAAGGACUAUGUCACCGGUGGGGCUUGCCCCAGCAAGGCCACCAUCCCUGGGAAGACGGUCAUCGUGACGGGUGCCAACACAGGCAUCGGGAAGCAGACCGCCUUGGAACUGGCCAGGAGAGGAGGCAACAUCAUCCUGGCCUGCCGAGACAUGGAGAAGUGUGAGGCGGCAGCAAAGGACAUCCGCGGGGAGACCCUCAAUCACCAUGUCAACGCCCGGCACCUGGACUUGGCUUCCCUCAAGUCUAUCCGAGAGUUUGCAGCAAAGAUCAUUGAAGAGGAGGAGCGAGUGGACAUUCUAAUCAACAACGCGGGUGUGAUGCGGUGCCCCCACUGGACCACCGAGGACGGCUUCGAGAUGCAGUUUGGCGUUAACCACCUGGGUCACUUUCUCUUGACAAACUUGCUGCUGGACAAGCUGAAAGCCUCAGCCCCUUCGCGGAUCAUCAACCUCUCGUCCCUGGCCCAUGUUGCUGGGCACAUAGACUUUGACGACUUGAACUGGCAGACGAGGAAGUAUAACACCAAAGCCGCCUACUGCCAGAGCAAGCUCGCCAUCGUCCUCUUCACCAAGGAGCUGAGCCGGCGGCUGCAAGGCUCUGGUGUGACUGUCAACGCCCUGCACCCCGGCGUGGCCAGGACAGAGCUGGGCAGACACACGGGCAUCCAUGGCUCCACCUUCUCCAGCACCACACUCGCCAGCAAACCCCAAACAGGAACCUAUGGUUGGUGAUGGAUGUGCGUUCAGAAAGCAGGGAGGGAGGGGGAGUCAGAGGUGAGGGGGUCAUCAGCCAUAGCUGUCCGCUGCAUCACCCCCUCGCUAUCUCCAGGAAGCGUUCUGGGCUUUUCCUGUUGUGCAGUGUGGAAGUGCUCUAUCUUCAUUCAUAUCAAGGAAAGUCAAAGGACAAACUAAAGCCGGCAGCGUCUUUCUGGCUUCCUAGUCAGGCUGUUCGGUAGCGGAGUGUCACCCUGAUUUCCAGCCCCGCAGCACACACAGUGAGAGCCUGCCUGGCGUGAUUCAGAGGCAACGUAUUUCCCAAGGUGGCUGUGAAGGAACCAGGGGGAUAAACACAGCCCGUGAACCGCACGCCAGAGGACAGGUCCGGCUGCCUGCCGCGGAGUCGUCACGGCGUGUCGCGUCUGAGCGCUUCUCCAAAGCACCCAAGUGGCACCCGGGGUGACAGUUACAUCAUCUUGAGUACAGUUCUCUCAAGGAAAAAGCAAGCCCAGCAUCUUCUGCCAUGGCAACCCUGGCUUGGAGCCUCCAUAAGAGAGAAGGCCCUAAGAAUAAUACCAUUUUCUUGCUCUAAGUUGCUCUUACGGGAAAGAAGUGAUAAUAUUCUUCCUAAACGCCAUCAUUCGUGCAUCCUUCCCACCUAUAUGUGUCACCGGAUCAUUCUCCGCCUGGGCGGGGCCGUCCUGUGCACUGCAGAAUGCUGAGCAGUGUCCUUGGCUUCGACCGACCACAUGCCAGGAGCACCCCAAUUUCUGCCAUCGGGUGAUUGACUUCACUGUUGCAUUUGAUUUUUUAUGUAUCUUUUAAAAGGACCCAAUAGGGCCAGGCACAGUGGCUCACACUUGUAAUCCCAGCACUUUGGGAGGCUGAGGUCGGUGGAUUGCUUGAGCCCAGGAGGAGUUCAAGACCAGCCUGGGCAACAUAGUGAAACCCCAACUCUACAAAAAACAAAUGUUUUAUUUUUAUUUAUUUUAGAUGGAGUUUCACUCUUGUUGCCCAGGCUGGAGUGCAGUGGCGCAAUCUCGGCUCACUGCAACUUCUGCCUCCCGGGUUCAAGCGAUUCUCCUGCCUCAGCCUCCUGAGUAUCUGGGAUUACAGGCAUGCGCCACCACACCCAGCUAAUUUUGUAUUUUUAGUAGAGAUGGCGUUUCUCCAUGUUGGUCAGGCUGGUCUCAAACUCCCGACCUCAGGUGAUCUGCCUGCCUCGGCCUCCCAGAGUGUUGGGAUUACAGGCGUGAGCCACCACGCCCAGCCGGGUUUAUAGUUUUAUAACCCUUAUGACAAAUCUCAUAGUAUUCUGCAGGGAUAAGCAUGAAACCACUCGUUCAAUAAGUGCAAACAAAAACGCCAACAAUUCUUAAGACAUUUCUAAUCUUAUUUUACCAAUAAUUUUAAAGCCAGCUUAUGUAUUAAAGAUUUAUAACUACUUUUAUUAACACGUUUAAAAUUCUAUGCAGCUUAAAGCAUUUAUAAUGGAUAAAACUGCCAAUACUGAGUGCCUGACAUAAUAUUUGAAAGGUGGCAGGCAUUCAACCAUGGUCACUGAAUGAGAGAUGUAGGGAAGAUGAUGGCAGGGAGGUUUUUAGAUAUCAACACCCUGAUAGUUCUCAUUUUAACCACCUGUAAGUGCACAUACAAGUCAACGGCACUGGCCGGGCGCGGUGGCUCAUGCCUGUAUUCCCAGCACUUUGGGAGGCCAAAUCACAAGGUCAGGAGAUCGAGACCAUCCUGGCUAACACGGUGAAACCCCGUCUCUACUAAAAAUACAAAAAAUCAACUAGGCAUGGUGGCACGCACCUGUAGUCCCAGCUACUCAGGAGGCUGAGGCAGGAGAAUCGCUUGAACCUGGGAGGCGGAGGUUGCGGUGAGCCAAGAUCGCGCCACUGCACUCCAGCCUCGGCGACAGAGUGAGACUCCGUCUCAAAAAACCAAAAAACAAAAAACAGUCAAUGGCAUUAAAUAUAAAUACAUUUACAGUGUUGUGUAACCAUCACCACUAUGGAUCCCCCAGACUUUGUCAUCAUCUUCAACCUAAGCGCUCCCUAUUAAAUAGUAACUCCCCACUUUUCCCAGGCCUUGGCAACCACCAUUCUAAUCCCUGUCUCUAUGAAUUUGACUCCUCUCGAUACCUCAGAUAAGCGGCACAAUGCAGUAUUUAUCUGUCAAGUCCGGAAUAUUUCCUUUAGCAUAAUGUCUUCAAGGUCCAUCACGUUGUAGCAUGUAUCUGAAUUUAUUCUUUUAUAAUAUUUUUUAUUUUUUGGAGACAGAAUCUCGCUCUGUCACCCAGGCUGGAGUGCAAUGGCGCGAUCUCGGCUCACCGCAACUUCCGCGUCCCGGGUUCAAGCCAUUCUCCUGUCUCAGCCUCCGGAGUAGCUGGGACUACAGGUGCCUGCCGCCAUGCCCGGCUAUUUUUUUUUUGUAUUUUUUGGGGGUUUUACUGUGUUGCCCAGGCUGGUCUUGAACUGCUGAGCUCAGGCAAUCUGCCUGCCUCAGCCUCCUAAAGUACUAGGAUUACAGGCAUGGGCCACCACGCCCGGCCUUAUUUUUAUUUUUGAGACAGUCUCACUCUGCCGCCCAGGCUGGAGUGCAGUGGUGCGAUCUCGGCUUACCGCAAUCUCUGCCUCCCAGGUUCAAGCGAUUCUCAUGCCUCCGUCUCCCAAGUAGCUGGGAUUACAGGCACCUGCCACCAUGCCCGGCUAAUUUAACGCCCAGCUAAUUUUUGUAUUUUUAGUAGAGAUGGGGUUUCACCAUGUUAACCAGGCUGGUCUCGGACUCCUGACCUCAGGUGAUCCGCCCGCCUCGGCCUCCCAAAGUGCUGGGAUUACAGGCGUGAGCCACUGUGCCUGGCUGAUUUUUAUUCUUUUAGUUAAGGCUGGUUGAUAUUACCUUGUGUGUAUAUACCACAUGUUGUUUAUCCAUUGUUGUUGAUGGACAUGUGGGUGGUUUCACCUUUUGGCUAUUGUGAAUAAAGCUGCUAUGAACACUGUGUACAAAUAUGUUAGAGACCCUGUUUUCAGUUCUUUUAGGUGUGUACCCCGAAGUGGAAUUGCUGGAUUUUAUGGCAAUCCCACGUUUAACUUCUGGAGGAGCUGCUGGAACUGUUUUCCACAGCAGGGGCGCCAUGUUACGUCCCUGCCAGCAAUGCACGCGCAGUUCAAUUUCUCUGCAUACUCACCAAUAUCUGCUGUUUUCCAUUAAAAAAAAU